ACGCAUGGUCCCAGCGCGCGUGCGCCCCUGAAGGCGGGUUCCGGUGGCAGCGCCGGGGUCUCAGACCCUGAGGAGACUGAGCCCAGCGCCAGGCGACCGGUCCCCGCCGCCGCCGCCCCUGCGCGGGAGAUCCCCCCUGCUUAGUCCGCGCCCGAGCCCCCGUCCGUGGGAACAGACAAGGGGCCUCCGCAGCGCCUCACAACCCCCGACCAGGUCCAGCGGCGGGGGACUCGGCCGUGGAGGGCGCUGUUCGGUCUGGAUGGCUCCCCCCAUCAGCGGGAGGCUACACCCCCCACCAGCAGGGGCAAGAGGAGCAGCGGGAUGGGAGCAGGCCAACGUCCUGCGGCCUGGUUGAGCUCGCACUGACAAUCGCAGGCCCAGUAACCCGCAGGUCACCGCGCUCCCCACCUGCGUUGCUGACGGUGACAUCGUCAGGGGAGGGGGGCGCGCCUUCCCAGAGGCUCAGGUCGCGAGGGUAGCCGGGGUCCGGGCGCGCCGCCGCCUCGUCGUAGCGCCAGUACUGCCGGCCGCGGACCAGGUAGGUCUUCCCGUUCUGUGGCCACGAGAACACGGCGUCCACCUCCUCUCCCGGGGGCAGCCCCAGCUCCGUGAGCGGCCGCGCCCCGCCCUCCAGCUGCCGGUCCUGGAACACCCAGAACUGGGGCCCUGCAGGGUGGAGGCCGGGAGGUCAGGGGUGGGCUCCCCGCGCCGGCCCCAGCGCGCCCCGCCGCCGGCCCCACUCACCGCUAAAGAGGAGGAUUCGGCCGUCUCGGUGCCGAGCAUAGGCGGCCUGCACCACCCUCACCUGGGCGGGCAGCCCCUCCCAGAAGCGGUGCAGCCGUGCGGGUCGCGGGGACACCAGCUGUCCGGAGGGCUGGAGGCGCCAGAACCAGGGGCCUGCAGGGGACAAAGGGGUUCGCAGGAAGGCAUGAGACAGCAGGAGGUCUCCUCCCCCAGGGUGUGUGGCUGGGUGGGGAGGGGUCCCAUCUGGAAAUCAAGGGCGCAAUGGAUCUAGGGUGACCAGCCCAUCCUGGCCCGCCUGAGACUUUUCCCUUUUUAGCGCUAAAAGUGCCAGGGCCUUGCCUGGUGGCUCAGACCUGUAAUGCCAGCACAUUGGGAGGCUGACACCGGAGAAUCACCUGAGCCAGGAGAUUGAGCCCAGCCUGGGCAAUAUAGUGAGACUCCAUCUCUACAAAAUAAUAAAAUAAAUUACUAGCAAGGCGUGGUGGCAUGUGCCUGUGGUCCCAGCUACCAGGGAGGCUGAGGUGGGAGGAUCGCUUGAGCCCAGUAUUUUGAGGCUGCAGUGAGCCAUGAUCACACCACUGCACUGCGGCCCAGGCAACAAAGCAAGACCCUGUCUCAAAGAAGAAAAAAGUUCCGCUUCCAGGGUAAGCCCACAGCCCCAGUGGGUCACUGGAAGUGGGCAGGAAACCAACAUAUAUGAGGCCAAGUGAAAUGACUCACCUUUGAAGAAGAAAGUUUCCCCUCGGAUGUUGGCGAUGGCGUCAAAAUUGCCCUCACAUCGAUCAGGGAUGGGGAAGGAUGGGCUGGGGAGGAAAGGAGAGGUGAGUAGAGAGGGGGGUUUGUUUUCUCCAAGGCAGGGACCCCCACCAUCCCCAUCUCAGAGGACACUGAGGCUGGGCAGCUGGUCACCCAAGGUCUCCGAGUUGGUGGGGGACUCACCUGUGUGUGGGCGAGGCCGGGGGCUGGGGCGGAGGAGCCAGGGGUUUCCUUGUGGGCUUGUCAUAUGGGGUUUGGGGCGCCUUCCCUGUGAGGAAAGAGUCAGGCAGGUGUGCGUCCCCUGGCCCUGCUGCAGAGGACACUGGAUGGGGCAAUGAUGGUUUCGCGGCAGGUCCCUCUCCCCCUACCAUAGAGUUGCUGCAGGCCAUCGCGGUCAUCCUGAGACAGGCGGUACUUGUCAGGGUCGCCCACCGGACCCUGGUAGAAGGGCCUCAUAAUGGAGUUGGGGGCUGAGGAGUGGCCCAGGCCCAGGGCGUGGCCAAACUCAUGGACAGCCACGGCAAACAGCUCAGGCGCUCAGGACUGCCAGGACCCAGAGGAUUCACACGCCAGCCCCGGCUGAAGCCCAGCUCCUCAUCAACCGGUGAGCCGCCUGCCAGCUCCUGCUCCAGCUGCUGAGAGGCCUGAAGAGACCAAGACAGAGACACAGCCCCGCAGCACCACAGGGAGGCCCCAGUUACCCCAUGCGGAUGAGUUUCAUGGCCAUCUCUAACUAAGGACAGGACAUCGAUGUCAUCUGUAACUUCCGGUGCACUGGGGCACACAGCUGCAUCUCCCCAUGCUCACCUCCUGCCUCUUGCUCUGCCCAGUGUGAGGACUCAGCCUGGAUCACCUCCUCCAGGACAAGAACAACCUACCAUCAUCUGUCCGUCCAAUCUACCCACCCAUCCAUCUCUGCCUCUGGCCAUGCAUCCGUCCGUCCAUCCAUCCCCGCCUCUGUGCAUGCAUCUGUCCAUCCAUCCCCGCCUCUGUGCAUGCAUCUGUGCAUCCAUCCAUCCCUGCCUCUGUGCAUGCAUCUGUCCAUCCAUCCCCGCCUCUGUGCAUGCAUCUGUCCAUCCAUCCCCACCUCUGUGCAUGCAUCUGUCCGUACAUCCAUCCCUGCCUCUGUGCAUGCAUCUGUCCAUUCAUCCCUGCCUCUGUGCAUGCAUCUGUCCAUCCAUCCAUCCCCGCCUCUGUGCAUGCAUCUGUCCAUCCAUCCCUGCCUCUGUGCAUGCAUCUGUCCAUUCAUCCCUGCCUCUGUGCAUGCAUCUGUCCAUCCAUCCAUCCCUGCCUCUGUGCAUGCAUCUGUCCAUUCAUCCCUGCCUCUGUGCAUGCAUCUGUCCAUCCAUCCAUCCCUGCCUCUGUGCAUGCAUCUGUCCAUUCAUCCCUGCCUCUGUGUAUGCAUCUGUCCAUCCAUCCAUCCCCACCUCUGUGCAUGCAUCUGUCCAUCCAUCCCCGCCUCUGUGCAUGCAUCUGUCCGUCCAUCCAUCCCUGCCUCUGUGCAUGCAUCUGUCCGUCCAUUCAUCCCUGCCUCUGUGCAUGCAUCUGUCCAUUCAUCCAUCCCUGACUCUGUGCAUGCAUCUGUCCAUCCAUCCAUCCUUGCCUCUAUGCAUGCAUUUGUCCGUCCAUCCAUCCCUGCCUCUGUGCAUGCAUCCAUACCUGCCUCUGUGCAUGCAUCUGUCAGUCUAUCAAUCCCCGAUCCCUUCUUUGUAAUGGUGUUGAGCGCUCACAACUCCCUCAUCCUAAGACGCUCGUUGGAUCCAUUCCCUCCCCUCACCCCAUGCUGCUCUCUGCCCUCCCUUCCCGGUCAAGUUCUCCAGCCAGUGGUCUCAACUCAAUCUUCACUUCCCCCGCUCCUCUCACACCUAUCCCCACUGCAUUCUAAAUUCUUCCCCAACGCGCUGGGCCUACAGGCACUAAAAAGGUCACUUUGUCCCUGGAUGACCAAACACAGGCCAAUGUAACUUACUGGGCUUGUUUUGCCCCAGCCACAGCUGACCACUUCCUCCUUCACUCUUGUUGUUGAUCACCUUUGGGCUUAGUCUUUCUCCAUCUCUGUUGAGUCCUUCUCCCCUGCCACCUACUCCUUCAUGCUGGGGUUCUCUGUAGCUCUGUACCUGACAGUCACGUUCCACCCUUUCCUCCCAGAAGCUCGCCAACCCCCGUGGACUGCUGGCUCUCAAGGCGGCCGCUAGCCCAGCUCCGACAGCAGCUGACAAUGCACAGUAUGCGGCCCAGGGCAGGCCCUGUGCUGAGAGGCAUGGGUGAAUGGCUCAUUUCAUCGGCAAGCCCACGCCACCAGCAGGCGCCGUUCUCCUCGCAUUUCUCAGGCGAGGAACCUGAGACAAUGAGGUUAAGGAAGUUGUUCAUUACAAGUGGAAGAACCCUGACUUACUUGAAUUCAGCUUUGAAGCCCA